ACCUUAGCAACCAGCGCGGCUCCCACCAUGGCUGAAGAAGAGGAAACUGCUGCUCUCACGGAGAAGGUUAUCCGGACCCAGAGGGUGUUUAUAAACCUGUUGGAUUCCUACAGCAGCGGAAACAUCGGGAAGUUUCUAUCUAACUGUGUAGUUGGGGCUUCGCUUGAAGAAAUUACAGAGGAAGAGGAAGAGGAAGAUGAAAAUAAGUCAGCUAUGCUGGAAGCUUCCUCAACCAAAGUGAAGGAAGGCACAUUCCAGAUUGUGGGCACGCUGUCCAAGCCUGACAGCCCGCGGCCUGACUUUGCGGUGGAGACGUACUCUGCCAUCUCUCGAGAAGACCUUCUCAUGCGCCUGCUGGAGUGUGAUGUUAUUAUUUAUAACAUCACUGAGAGCUCACAGCAAAUGGAGGAAGCCAUCUGGGCAGUCUCUGCACUCAGUGAAGAAGUCAGCCACUUUGAAAAGCGAAAGCUAUUUAUUUUACUGUCGACGGUGAUGACUUGGGCGCGCUCCAAAGCCCUGGACCCCGAGGAUUCUGAGGUUCCAUUCACUGAAGAAGAUUAUCGAAGAAGAAAGUCUCAUCCUAAUUUUCUGGACCACAUAAAUGCUGAAAAAAUGGUUCUCAAAUUUGGAAAAAAGGCCAGAAAAUUUGCAGCAUACGUAGUUGCUGCUGGACUCCAGUAUGGAGCGGAAGGAGGCAUGUUACACACAUUUUUUAAGAUGGCUUGGUUGGGCGAGAUUCCUGCAUUACCAGUUUUUGGCGAUGGAACAAAUGUAAUUCCAACAAUCCAUGUUCUUGAUCUAGCAGGAGUGAUACAAAACGUCAUAGAUCACGUGCCAAAGCCUCACUACCUGGUUGCUGUGGAUGAGUCUGUUCAUACCCUGGAAGACAUAGUCAAGUGUAUCAGUAAAAAUACUGGCCCUGGGAAAAUCCAGAAAAUACCCAGAGAAAAUGCAUACCUAACCAAGGACUUAACGCAAGAUUGUCUUGACCAUUUACUGGUCAACUUAAGAAUGGAAGCGCUCUUUGUGAAGGAGAAUUUUAAUAUUCGAUGGGCUGCCCAAACAGGAUUUGUGGAAAAUAUCAACACUAUCCUCAAGGAGUACAAGCAAAGCAGAGGAUUGAUGCCAAUCAAGAUCUGCAUUCUUGGUCCCCCUGCUGUGGGAAAAUCCAGUAUUGCUAAAGAAUUGGCCAACUACUACAAACUGCAUCACAUCCAACUGAAGGAUGUCAUUUCUGAAGCCAUAGCAAAACUGGAGGCGAUUGUUGCCCCUAACGAUGUAGGGGAAGGAGAAGAAGAAGUCGAAGAGGAAGAGGAGGAGGAGAAUGUGGAAGAUGCACAGGAGCUCCUAGAUGGCAUCAAGGAGAGCAUGGAGCAGAAUGCAGGUCAACUAGACGAUCAAUAUAUAAUUAGAUUUAUGAAAGAAAAGCUAAAAUCAAUGCCUUGCAGGAAUCAAGGUUAUAUUUUGGAUGGAUUCCCAAAGACCUAUGAUCAAGCAAAAGACCUGUUCAAUCAGGAAGAUGAGGAGGAGGAAGAUGAUGUCAGAGGCAGAAUGUUUCCCUUUGAUAAAUUAAUUAUACCUGAAUUCGUUUGUGCACUGGAUGCUUCGGAUGAGUUUCUGAAGGAGCGUGUGAUAAACCUUCCUGAGAGCAUCGUGGCGGGGACCCACUACAGCCAAGACCGAUUCCUCCGGGCUCUGAGCAACUACCGGGACAUCAAUAUCGACGAUGAGACUGUCUUCAACUAUUUUGAUGAACUUGAAAUUCACCCGAUACAUAUUGAUGUAGGAAAACUUGAAGAUGCUCAGAAUAGACUUGCUAUCAAACAGCUCAUCAAAGAGAUUGGGGAGCCUCGAAAUUAUGGUUUAACAGACGAAGAAAAGGCAGAAGAGGAGCGGAAGGCUGCGGAGGAGCGGCUGGCCAGGGAGGCUGCUGAGGAAGCAGAACGCGAGCACCAGGAGGCCGUGGAGAUGGCAGAGAAGAUAGCUCGCUGGGAGGAGUGGAAUAAACGACUGGAGGAAGUGAAAAGAGAAGAAAGAGAAUUACUGGAGGCUCAGUCAAUUCCCCUGAGAAACUAUUUAAUGACCUAUGUGAUGCCAACUCUUAUUCAGGGCCUGAAUGAAUGUUGCAACGUCCGACCCGAAGACCCUGUUGAUUUUCUGGUUGGAAUGCAAUGGCACAAUCUCGGCUUACUGCAACCUCCACCUCCCGGGUUCAAGUGAUUCUCCUGCCUUAGCCUCCCAAGUAGCUGGGAUUACAGGCGCCUGCCACCACACUCAGCUAAUGUUUUGUAUUUUAGUAGAGAGGAAGUUUCACCAUGUUGACCAGGCUGGUCUCGAACUCCUGACCUCAAGUGAUCCACCCGCCUCAGCCUCCCAAAGUGCUGGGAUUACAGGCAUGAGCCACCAAGCUUGGCCCAGGAUGAUUUUUAAAUUGUAAACAUUACUAAUACAAAUACAUGACUAAUAAUAACUUGUAAACUGUUGACUUGUCUUUUUUUAAAUUGUAGGCAGAAUAUCUCUUCAAGAACAAUCCUGAAGCACAGUGAAACUUGAAAGAUCUGGUAUUAUCUACCUUUACAGAACCACAGAUCACUUAUUAUACUUUGAAAAAUUGCUUUGAAAAAUGCUUUUCCAGUUCUUAGAAAAUUCUUUUUUUGUAGACAAAUAUUCUAUAAACUAGAAUCUCUAUUAAAAGCUAUAUGACAUGACUAUGUCAUUAAAACUAUAUUUGAAAUGUAAAUUGAUAAAGACAUUUGUGCAUAGCUCAUGAGACAAAUACUGAUUUAAUAUUUUAUUCUUUAGUCAGAUCUAAAUAUACCGCUUCUGUACACUAAUGUUUAUAGGUAUUUAUAGCAUGAAGAAAAUCAGACUAUAUAUUGUAGACUAUGUAUUAUUCUAACAUGUAGGCUAAUUUACAUGACUUGUUAUCGCCCCAAUAACAAUGUUAUUAGAAAUGGAAAUAAAUUGAAGUGAUUUAUGCCUGUUGACUCACAGUAAAUCAGACAAGAUUGGUGCCUGUAAGGUGGCUUUUUUUUUUUUUUUUUUUAAAUGAAGCAAUGGUUAGGGAAAGGUUGCUUUGAGUUCAGGGUCAGGAUCCCAGACAAUGAAUCGGAGAGAACUGUAAACCUUUAGGCGGAGAAAUCUGCAUAACAGGAUAAUUCCAAUCUUUGUGAUAAGUGAGAAGUUGCUAAAUAUUUUCAACACACUUUAUAACAUAGGCAUAAGUUAUCAAUCCUAUAGUCUUUUCCAGUUCUAAAAAUCCCAUAAGAUUCCUAGAAUUACCCUAAAUGAGAAAUUAGUUUAGGUUUAAUGGCAUAUGUAUUUUAUCUCUUUAAAUAAUGUAACCUAAUAUAACUGCCCGACUUUUUAUUUGUGCUAAAAUACAUGUAACAUAAAAUUGACCACUGUAACCAUUUUAAAGUGUAUAAUUCAGUGGCACUAAGUUCAUUCACAAUGAUCUGCAGCCACCACUAUCUAGUCCAGAACUUUCUCAUCACCCCAAAUGGAAACCCAGCACCUAUUAGGCAGUCACGCUCCAUUAUUCCCUCCCCCCAGUUCCAGGCAACCACGAAUCUGCUUUCUGUCUCUAUGGAUUUACCUAUUAUAAAUAAAACCAUAUAAUGGGUGGUC